GCAGUCGGCGGUCGGCGUGGGGCGCUAUGCCGGGGCGGCACGUUUCUCGAGUCCGGGCAUUGUACAAGCGCGUCUUGCAGCUGCACCGUGUUCUGCCCCCGGACCUCAAAUCCCUGGGCGACCAGUACGUGAAAGACGAAUUUAGGAGACAUAAGACCGUUGGUUCUGACGAGGCACAGCGUUUCUUGCAAGAAUGGGAGGUGUAUGCAACAGCGUUAUUGCAACAGGCUAACGAAAACAGACAAAAUUCAACUGGAAAAGCAUGUUUUGGCACCUUCCUCCCAGAAGAAAAACUUAAUGACUUUCGUGAUGAACAAAUUGGACAGUUGCAGGAGCUGAUGCAAGAAGCCACAAAACCCAAUAGGCAAUUUAGUAUUUCUGAGUCUAUGAAACCAAAAUUUUAGUCUAUACAACAAAGCUUAAUAAGACAUGCAAAAAUUUAGAACCCCUACUUUAACUGUCAUUGGUUUUUGAAAUAUAUUUAAGCUUUGAAAACACCUGUUAUUAAUGAAAUACUCUUUUAUUUUGGAUAUUAUGAUUGCAGUAUAUGGAUCAAGAUCACUAGUGACAAUUGAAAAAAACUAUUGGAAUAAUAGCACUUGUAUGAAAUUCAGUUUUGGAACUAAACAGCAAAUUUCUAGAAUUUUGCUGAAAAUGUUUUAAAAUGCUAUUCUCAUCCAGCCAUAUUAGUCUUCUGGCUUUUCUUUAGCUUCAUCAAAUAAGCAUGUUGUGAUAAUGAUAGAUGUACAAUUCCAACAAGGUUAUUAUUUUUUAAAUACAUUGUCAUUCUGAACAUUUUAUCACUUCUAGUUUAAUAAUACAUACAUGAUUUUUCUUCUGAAUGUCUCUUCUCCCUGCAUCACUGUUCAUUCACAAUGAAAGGUUAGGAAGAAGCUUUAAAAUUCACUAUUUUACUAUCAAUCAUUUGUAUAAUAAACUAUACAAAGUAUAA